GGACAAACCAGCCAGCCUCUCCAGAGCAGGCGUGUGAUCUCUGUACCCCCGCAGUGGUCAGAAUAUGGAGAACUUCUCACUCCUCAGCAUCUCUGGACCUCCAAUCUCUUCCUCCGCCCUGAGUGCUUUUCCCGACAUUAUGUUCUCUCGUGCCACCAGCCUGCCAGACAUUGCAAAGACAGCAGUACCCACUGAGGCAUCCAGCCCAGCUCAGGCCCUGCCACCCCAGUACCAAAGCAUCAUUGUCAGGCAAGGGAUACAGAACACAGCGCUCUCACCAGACUGCAGCUUGGGGGAUACCCAGCACGGAGAGAAGCUGAGGCGGAACUGCACUAUCUACCGGCCCUGGUUCUCCCCCUACAGCUACUUCGUGUGUGCAGACAAAGAGAGCCAGCUGGAGGCCUAUGACUUCCCAGAGGUGCAGCAGGAUGAGGGCAAGUGGGACAACUGCCUUUCUGAGGACAUGGCUGAGAACAUCUGUUCGUCCUCUUCCUCCCCAGAGAACACUUGCCCUCGAGAAGCCACCAAGAAAUCCAGGCAUGGCCUGGACUCCAUCACAUCCCAGGACAUCCUAAUGGCUUCCAGGUGGCACCCAGCACAGCAGAAUGGCUACAAGUGCGUGGCCUGCUGCCGCAUGUACCCCACCCUGGACUUCCUCAAGAGCCACAUCAAGAGGGGCUUCAGGGAGGGCUUCAGCUGCAAGGUGUACUACCGCAAGCUCAAAGCCCUCUGGAGCAAGGAGCAGAAGGCCCGGCUGGGAGACAGGCUCUCCUCCGGCAGCUGCCAGGCCUUCAAUAGUCCUGCUGAACACCUUAGGCAAAUUGGCGGUGAAGCCUACUUAUGUCUCUAGAGAGAUGCCAAUAAAGUUAGUCACAGCCUUCUGUCCAGUCUGAGGUCACCCCGCACAGCCUGCUGUCCUUCCCAGAACCCGGCUCUCAUCACCUUUGGCUAAUGGUUGCCUAGCAACACCAGGCACACACCCUCCCCUUUCUCUCUUUUAAAAAUAAAGACAAUACUUGAAGUUUGGGAAAAUCAUCUAAGAUAGAGGUUCUCAAAGGUGCCCAGCUGGCAGUACCAGCAACCCCUGGGAACUCUCAGGCCCUCCUCAGACCUACUGAAUCAGAAACUAUGGGUCUGGGGCUGGCGGUCUAUGUCCUAACCAGCCCUCCAGGUGACUCUGAUGCAGCUCAGCUGUGAGAAGCACUGCUCUAGGAUUCUGGCCUCUGCUUGGUCCCUAUGUGGUCAGUCCUUGCCCCACCCUGGGAAGAAGGGGCUGGAUGCCCUUUCCUAUUUGCAUGGGGAAGAAUCUCUGCAGUUUUAAAGGCUUCUUUGACGGUAGAUCUUCUGAGGGGGGAAUGUGGAGGAAAAUAUGCCUCUGAGUAUAAGGCAGGUAAGAGGCAGAUGGGGCUGAGCUCACCCGGGACUGAGCUCUCAGGCACUACCAUCAUUCACUUAGAACAGCCAUCCAGUGCUGGGGCAGAAUAGAAUCAGUUUUGACCCAGGAGACGUCUUUUCUUGGCUGCUUUGAGCCAGGUGAAAAUAGGCAGGUAAACAUGGGAACCUAUUGCUUCCUGUUACCAAGUAAUGUGUCCAGUGGGCAGCCCUGACUCUGCCUCCAUUUCUGAGUGAACCUCCUGGUCCAUCUGACCCAGAAAGAUGGAUAAGCAUCAGGGAUGCAGCAGAGACAUCUAUCUU